GUCCCAGGUGGGCCUGGAUCCUUCCAGCUCAUUCUUUGCCUGCGCCGUCCCUCGUUCCAUGGCCCAGUCCUCCCCGGGGACCCUGAGCCUGGAAGCCCCGGACCACUGGAACCUUGAACCCACCAGCUGGCUGUACCCGGAGCCGUGGCAGCAGCCCUCAUCCCCAUGGCGGCCAUCCCAGCCCUGGACCCAGAGGCCGAGCCCAGCAUGGACGUGAUUUUGGUGGGAUCCAGUGAGCUCUCAAGCUCCGUUUCACCCGGGACAGGCAGAGAUCUUAUUGCAUAUGAAGUCAAGGCUAACCAGCGAAAUAUAGAAGACAUCUGCAUCUGCUGCGGAAGUCUCCAGGUUCACACACAGCACCCUCUGUUUGAGGGAGGGAUCUGCGCCCCAUGUAAGGACAAGUUCCUGGAUGCCCUCUUCCUGUACGACGAUGACGGGUACCAAUCCUACUGCUCCAUCUGCUGCUCCGGAGAGACGCUGCUCAUCUGCGGAAACCCUGAUUGCACCCGAUGCUACUGCUUCGAGUGUGUGGAUAGCCUGGUCGGCCCCGGGACCUCGGGGAAGGUGCACGCCAUGAGCAACUGGGUGUGCUACCUGUGCCUGCCGUCCUCCCGAAGCGGGCUGCUGCAGCGUCGGAGGAAGUGGCGCAGCCAGCUCAAGGCCUUCUACGACCGAGAGUCGGAGAAUCCCCUUGAGAUGUUCGAAACCGUGCCUGUGUGGAGGAGACAGCCAGUCCGGGUGCUGUCCCUUUUUGAAGACAUCAAGAAAGAGCUGACGAGUUUGGGCUUUUUGGAAAGUGGUUCUGACCCGGGACAACUGAAGCAUGUGGUUGAUGUCACAGACACAGUGAGGAAGGAUGUGGAGGAGUGGGGACCCUUCGAUCUUGUGUACGGCGCCACACCUCCCCUGGGCCACACCUGUGACCGUCCUCCCAGCUGGUACCUGUUCCAGUUCCACCGGCUCCUGCAGUACGCACGGCCCAAGCCAGGCAGCCCCAGGCCCUUCUUCUGGAUGUUCGUGGACAAUCUGGUGCUGAACAAGGAAGACCUGGACGUCGCAUCUCGCUUCCUGGAGAUGGAGCCAGUCACCAUCCCAGAUGUCCACGGCGGAUCCUUGCAGAAUGCUGUCCGCGUGUGGAGCAACAUCCCAGCCAUAAGGAGCAGCAGGCACUGGGCUCUGGUUUCGGAAGAAGAAUUGUCCCUGCUGGCCCAGAACAAGCAGAGCUCGAAGCUCGCGGCCAAGUGGCCCACCAAGCUGGUGAAGAACUGCUUUCUCCCCCUAAGAGAAUAUUUCAAGUAUUUUUCAACAGAACUCACUUCCUCUUUAUAAAUGAGUCACUAUACUGUGAAGAAAAAGACUUUUCCUAGAACAAAGGCAACUUUCCUCA